GCAGUGUGAGUAACACACUGAAGCCAGAAGCUGUGGGCUGUGGGGAAGUGGCUGCAUCGCCACCCAAGGGACCCUGGACUUUGCCAGACGUCAGGGUUGAGAGGAGCCACUAGCACCAUCCCAGAGCUGUCAGCACCGGCCUCAGCCCAGGCGGCUCUCUCCCUGAGCUUCCUGUACCCUGACCCUCUCCAGCCUCAGACCUGAGACAGGGCUGGACAAGGAAGCAGAGAGCAGAAGAAAAGCAGAAGCGAAGCUCAGAUCUGCUGGGAGGAGAUUACAUUUUGUCCCCUCCUGGGGUCUUGCACAGUGGCAGGUGACAUUCGUGUUACAGGAAUGACUGCCAGGGCCUGGGCCUCGUGGCGGUCUUCAGCUCUGCUCCUCCUGCUUGUCCCAGGCUAUUUUCCUCUGAGCCACCCCAUGACCGUGGCGGGCCCCGUGGGGGGAUCCCUGAGUGUGCAGUGUCGCUAUGAGAAGGAACACAGGACCCUCAACAAAUUCUGGUGCAGACCACCACAGAUUCUCCGAUGUGACAAGAUUGUGGAGACCAAAGGGUCAGCAGGGAAAAGGAAUGGCCGAGUGUCCAUCAGGGACAGUCCUGCAAACCUCAGCUUCACAGUGACCCUGGAGAAUCUCACAGAGGAGGACGCAGGCACCUACUGGUGUGGGGUGGAUACACCGUGGCUCCGAGACUUUCAUGAUCCCAUUGUCGAGGUUGAGGUGUCCGUGUUCCCGGGUGAGCCCCUCCUUUUCUCAGCACCAGGCCUGCCUGAGCCUAGGGCUGGUCAUUCUGUCCCUGAAGAAAGAAGUGGAACAGGAGGGUGUGAGCCUGGGGGUUGCCGGGACGACCACAGCCUCCAGCCCCCAGAGCUCCAUGGGCACCUCAGGUCCUCCCACGAAGCUGCCCGUGCACACCUGGCCCAGCGUGACCAGAAAGGACAGCCCCGAACCCAGCCCACACCCUGGCUCCCUGUUCAGCAAUGUCCGCUUCCUGCUCCUGGUCCUCUUGGAGCUGCCCCUGCUCCUGAGCAUGCUGGGUGCCGUCCUCUGGGUGAACAGACCUCAGAGAAGCUCUAGAAGCAGGCAGAAUUGGCCCAAGGGUGAGAACCAGUAGCAUCUGCUGUCCAUCAAGGCCCUGUGCUGCAACAGAGCCCCUCUGGGGGACUGGAAUGACCUCCUGACCACUCCCUCCCGGGCUGCUCUCUCCACAUCUCCUGGAAUCCUUUGUGAGCCUCCUUCAGCCUUUUCCCUGUGCCCGAUCCUCAUGUGUCACAUGUGAACCUGACGGACAUGGACGCCCUGAGCUGUGAGUCCACGUCUCAUGUGCACGCCCCGGCCAGCUAAGCCUCGGGCCGUCAGCAAUACCUCUGAGUGCCCGGAUGCCCUCCCUGCACCCUUCCAUUUCUCCAGGAGCCUGGCACUGCUUCCUCCACCGUUUUCACAGGGAGAAGCAGGUCUAGGACUCCCCUGCACCUUUGCCACCAUAAUGGCCCACACUCCCUGGGUCCAGGAGUGUAGAAUAUGCGGCUGCUUCCAUUUGCUGAGUGUGUCGAUUCAAUGAUGCUUUCAAACUUUAAUAAAUGACAAUGUGUAGGUUUGGGAUGUAUCAGGCCCACUCAGUCAGACCUGA